UCCCUGACUCCACCUCUUCUGCCACAAACGUCAGCAUGGUGGUAUCAGCCGGCCCUUGGUCCAGUGAGAAGGCAGAGAUGAACAUUCUAGAAAUCAACGAGACAUUGCGCCCCCAGCUGGCAGAGAAGAAACAGCAGUUCAGAAGCCUCAAAGAGAAAUGUUUUCUAACUCAACUGGCCGGCUUCCUGGCCAACCGACAGAAGAAAUACAAGUAUGAAGAGUGUAAAGACCUCAUAAAAUUUAUGCUGAGGAAUGAGCGACAGUUCAAGGAGGAGAAGCUUGCAGAGCAGCUGAAGCAAGCUGAGGAGCUCAGGCAAUAUAAAGUCCUAGUUCACUCUCAGGAACGAGAGCUGACCCAGCUAAGGGAGAAGUUACGGGAAGGGAGAGAUGCCUCCCGCUCAUUGUAUGAGCAUCUCCAGGCCCUCCUCACUCCGGAUGAGCCGGACAAGUCCCAGGGGCAGGACCUCCAAGAACAGCUGGCUGAGGGGUGUAGACUGGCACAGCACCUUGUCCAAAAGCUCAGCCCAGAAAAUGACGAAGAUGAGGAUGAAGAUGUUCAAGUUGAGGAGGCUGAGAAAGUACUGGAAUCAUCUGCCCCCAGGGAGGUGCAGAAGGCUGAAGAGAGCAAAGUCCCUGAGGACUCACUGGAGGAAUGUGCCAUCACUUGUUCAAAUAGCCACGGCCCUUGUGACUCCAACCAGCCUCACAAGAACAUCAAAAUCACAUUUGAGGAAGACGAAGUCAACUCAACUCUGGUUGUAGACAGAGAAUCCUCUCAUGAUGAAUGUCAGGAUGCUCUAAACAUUCUCCCAGUCCCUGGCCCCACCUCUUCUGCCACAAACGUCAGCAUGGUGGUAUCAGCCGGCCCUUUGUCCAGCGAGAAGGCAGAGAUGAACAUUCUAGAAAUCAAUGAGAAAUUGCGCCCCCAGCUGGCAGAGAAGAAACAGCAGUUCAGAAACCUCAAAGAGAAAUGUUUUCUAACUCAACUGUCCGGCUUCCUGGCCAACCAACAGAAGAAAUACAAAUAUGAAGAGUGCAAAGACCUCAUAAAAUUUAUGCUGAGGAAUGAGCGACAGUUCAAGGAGGAGAAGCUUGCAGAGCAGCUCAAGCAAGCUGAGGAGCUCAGGCAAUAUAAAGUCCUGGUUCACGCUCAGGAACGAGAGCUGACCCAGUUAAAGGAGAAGUUACGGGAAGGGAGAGAUGCCUCCCGCUCAUUGAAUGAGCAUCUCCAGGCCCUCCUCACUCCGUAUGAGCCGGACAAGUCCCAGGGGCAGGACCUCCAAGAACAGCUGGCUGAGGGGUGUAGACUGGCACAGCACCUUGUCCAAAAGCUCAGCCCAGAAAAUGACAACGAUGACGAUGAAGAUGUUCAAGUUGAGGUGGCUGAGAAAGUGCAGAAAUCAUCUGCCCCCAGGGAGAUGCAGAAGGCUGAAGAAAAGGAAGUCCCUGAGGACUCACUGGAGGAAUGUGCCAUCACUUAUUCAAAUAGCCAUGGCUCUUAUGACUCCAACCAGCCACAUAGGAAAACCAAAAUCACAUUUGAGGAAGACAAAGUCGACUCAACUCUCAUUGGCUCAUCCUCUCAUGUUGAAUGGGAGGAUGCUGUACACAUUAUUCCAGAAAAUGAAAGUGAUGAUGAGGAAGAGGAAGAAAAAGGGCCAGUGUCUCCCAGGAAUCUGCAGGAGUCUGAAGAGGAGGAAGUCCCCCAGGAGUCCUGGGAUGAAGGUUAUUCGACUCUCUCAAUUCCUCCUGAAAUGUUGGCCUCGUACCAGUCUUACAGCAGCACAUUUCACUCAUUAGAGGAACAGCAAGUCUGCAUGGCUGUUGACAUAGGCAGACAUCGGUGGGAUCAAGUGAAAAAGGAGGACCAAGAGGCAACAGGUCCCAGGCUCAGCAGGGAGCUGCUGGAUGAGAAAGGGCCUGAAGUCUUGCAGGACUCACAGGAUAGAUGUUAUUCAACUCCUUCAGGUUGUCUUGAACUGACUGACUCAUGCCAGCCCUACAGAAGUGCCUUUUACAUAUUGGAGCAACAGCGUGUUGGCUUGGCUAUUGACAUGGAUGAAAUUGAAAAGUACCAAGAAGUGGAAGAAGACCAAGACCCAUCAUGCCCCAGGCUCAGCAGGGAGCUGCUGGAUGAGAAAGAGCCUGAAGUCUUGCAGGACUCACUGGAUAGAUGUUAUUCGACUCCUUCAGGUUAUCUUGAACUGCCUGACUUAGGCCAGCCCUACAGCAGUGCUGUUUACUCAUUGGAGGAACAGUACCUUGGCUUGGCUCUUGACGUGGACAGAAUUAAAAAGGACCAAGAAGAGGAAGAAGACCAAGGCCCACCAUGCCCCAGGCUCAGCAGGGAGCUGCUGGAGGUAGUAGAGCCUGAAGUCUUGCAGGACUCACUGGAUAGAUGUUAUUCAACUCCUUCCAGUUGUCUUGAACAGCCUGACUCCUGCCAGCCCUAUGGAAGUUCCUUUUAUGCAUUGGAGGAAAAACAUGUUGGCUUUUCUCUUGACGUGGGAGAAAUUGAAAAGAAGGGGAAGGGGAAGAAAAGAAGGGGAAGAAGAUCAAAGAAGGAAAGAAGAAGGGGAAGAAAAGAAGGGGAAGAAGAUCAAAACCCACCAUGCCCCAGGCUCAGCAGGGAGCUGCUGGAUGAGAAAGGGCCUGAAGUCUUGCAGGACUCACUGGAUAGAUGUUAUUCAACUCCUUCAGGUUGUCUUGAACUGACUGACUCAUGCCAGCCCUACAGAAGUGCCUUUUAUGUAUUGGAGCAACAGCGUGUUGGCUUCGCUUUUGACAUGGAUGAAAUUGAAAAGUACCAAGAAGUGGAAGAAGACCAAGACCCAUCAUGCCCCAGGCUCAGCAGGGAGCUGCUGGAUGAGAAAGAGCCUGAAGUCUUGCAGGACUCACUGGAUAGAUGUUAUUCGACUCCUUCAGGUUAUCUUGAACUGCCUGACUUAGGCCAGCCCUACAGCAGUGCUGUUUACUCAUUGGAGGAACAGUACCUUGGCUUGGCUCUUGACGUGGACAGAAUUAAAAAGGACGAAGAAGAGGAAGAAGACCAAGACCCACCAUGCCCCAGGCUCAGCAGGGAGCUGCUGGAGGUAGUAGAGCCUGAAGUCUUGCAGGACUCACUGGAUAGAUGUUAUUCAACUCCUUCCAGUUGUCUUGAACAGCCUGACUCCUGCCAGCCCUAUGGAAGUUCCUUUUAUGCAUUGGAGGAAAACCAUGUUGGCUUUUCUCUUGACGUGGGAGAAAUUGAAAAGAAGGGGAAGGGGAAGAAAAGAAGGGGAAGAAGAUCAAAGAAGGAAAGAAGAAGGGGAAGAAAAGAAGGGGAAGAAGAUCAAAACCCACCAUGCCCCAGGCUCAGCAGGGAGCUGCUGGAAGAGAAAGGGCCUGAAGUCUUGCAGGACUCACUGGAUAGAUGUUAUUCAACUCCUUCAGGUUGUCUUGAACUGACUGACUCAUGCCAGCCCUACAGAAGUGCCUUUUAUGUAUUGGAGCAACAGCGUGUUGGCUUCGCUGUUGACAUGGAUGAAAUUGAAAAGUACCAAGAAGUGGAAGAAGACCAAGACCCAUCAUGCCCCAGGCUCAGCAGGGAGCUGCUGGAUGAGAAAGAGCCUGAAGUCUUGCAGGACUCACUGGAUAGAUGUUAUUCGACUCCUUCAGGUUAUCUUGAACUGCCUGACUUAGGCCAGCCCUACAGCAGUGCUGUUUACUCAUUGGAGGAACAGUACCUUGGCUUGGCUCUUGACGUGGACAGAAUUAAAAAGGACGAAGAAGAGGAAGAAGACCAAGACCCACCAUGCCCCAGGCUCAGCAGGGAGCUGCUGGAGGUAGUAGAGCCUGAAGUCUUGCAGGACUCACUGGAUAGAUGUUAUUCAACUCCUUCCAGUUGUCUUGAACAGCCUGACUCCUGCCAGCCCUAUGGAAGUUCCUUUUAUGCAUUGGAGGAAAAACAUGUUGGCUUUUCUCUUGACGUGGGAGAAAUUGAAAAGAAGGGGAAGGGGAAGAAAAGAAGGGGAAGAAGAUCAAAGAAGGAAAGAAGAAGGGGAAGAAAAGAAGGGGAAGAAGAUCAAAACCCACCAUGCCCCAGGCUCAGCAGGGAGCUGCUGGAAGAGAAAGGGCCUGAAGUCUUGCAGGACUCACUGGAUAGAUGUUAUUCAACUCCUUCAGGUUGUCUUGAACUGACUGACUCAUGCCAGCCCUACAGAAGUGCCUUUUAUGUAUUGGAGCAACAGCGUGUUGGCUUCGCUGUUGACAUGGAUGAAAUUGAAAAGUACCAAGAAGUGGAAGAAGACCAAGACCCAUCAUGCCCCAGGCUCAGCAGGGAGCUGCUGGAUGAGAAAGAGCCUGAAGUCUUGCAGGACUCACUGGAUAGAUGUUAUUCGACUCCUUCAGGUUAUCUUGAACUGCCUGACUUAGGCCAGCCCUACAGCAGUGCUGUUUACUCAUUGGAGGAACAGUACCUUGGCUUGGCUCUUGACGUGGACAGAAUUAAAAAGGACGAAGAAGAGGAAGAAGACCAAGACCCACCAUGCCCCAGGCUCAGCAGGGAGCUGCUGGAGGUAGUAGAGCCUGAAGUCUUGCAGGACUCACUGGAUAGAUGUUAUUCAACUCCUUCCAGUUGUCUUGAACAGCCUGACUCCUGCCAGCCCUAUGGAAGUUCCUUUUAUGCAUUGGAGGAAAAACAUGUUGGCUUUUCUCUUGACGUGGGAGAAAUUGAAAAGAAGGGGAAGGGGAAGAAAAGAAGGGGAAGAAGAUCAAAGAAGGAAAGAAGAAGGGGAAGAAAAGAAGGGGAAGAAGAUCAAAACCCACCAUGCCCCAGGCUCAGCAGGGAGCUGCUGGAUGAGAAAGGGCCUGAAGUCUUGCAGGACUCACUGGAUAGAUGUUAUUCAACUCCUUCAGGUUGUCUUGAACUGACUGACUCAUGCCAGCCCUACAGAAGUGCCUUUUAUGUAUUGGAGCAACAGCAUGUUGGCUUGGCUGUUGACAUGGAUGAAAUUGAAAAGUACCAAGAAGUGGAAGAAGACCAAGACCCAUCAUGCCCCAGGCUCAGCAGGGAGCUGCUGGAUGAGAAAGAGCCUGAAGUCUUGCAGGACUCACUGGAUAGAUGUUAUUCGACUCCUUCAGGUUAUCUUGAACUGCCUGACUUAGGCCAGCCCUACAGCAGUGCUGUUUACUCAUUGGAGGAACAGUACCUUGGCUUGGCUCUUGACGUGGACAGAAUUAAAAAGGACCAAGAAGAGGAAGAAGACCAAGGCCCACCAUGCCCCAGGCUCAGCAGGGAGCUGCUGGAGGUAGUAGAGCCUGAAGUCUUGCAGGACUCACUGGAUAGAUGUUAUUCAACUCCUUCCAGUUGUCUUGAACAGCCUGACUCCUGCCAGCCCUAUGGAAGUUCCUUUUAUGCAUUGGAGGAAAAACAUGUUGGCUUUUCUCUUGACGUGGGAGAAAUUGAAAAGAAGGGGAAGGGGAAGAAAAGAAGGGGAAGAAGAUCAAAGAAGGAAAGAAGAAGGGGAAGAAAAGAAGGGGAAGAAGAUCAAAACCCACCAUGCCCCAGGCUCAGCAGGGAGCUGCUGGAUGAGAAAGGGCCUGAAGUCUUGCAGGACUCACUGGAUAGAUGUUAUUCAACUCCUUCAGGUUGUCUUGAACUGACUGACUCAUGCCAGCCCUACAGAAGUGCCUUUUAUGUAUUGGAGCAACAGCAUGUUGGCUUGGCUGUUGACAUGGAUGAAAUUGAAAAGUACCAAGAAGUGGAAGAAGACCAAGACCCAUCAUGCCCCAGGCUCAGCAGGGAGCUGCUGGAUGAGAAAGAGCCUGAAGUCUUGCAGGACUCACUGGAUAGAUGUUAUUCGACUCCUUCAGGUUAUCUUGAACUGCCUGACUUAGGCCAGCCCUACAGCAGUGCUGUUUACUCAUUGGAGGAACAGUACCUUGGCUUGGCUCUUGACGUGGACAGAAUUAAAAAGGACCAAGAAGAGGAAGAAGACCAAGGCCCACCAUGCCCCAGGCUCAGCAGGGAGCUGCUGGAGGUAGUAGAGCCUGAAGUCUUGCAGGACUCACUGGAUAGAUGUUAUUCAACUCCUUCCAGUUGUCUUGAACAGCCUGACUCCUGCCAGCCCUAUGGAAGUUCCUUUUAUGCAUUGGAGGAAAAACAUGUUGGCUUUUCUCUUGACGUGGGAGAAAUUGAAAAGAAGGGGAAGGGGAAGAAAAGAAGGGGAAGAAGAUCAAAGAAGGAAAGAAGAAGGGGAAGAAAAGAAGGGGAAGAAGAUCAAAACCCACCAUGCCCCAGGCUCAGCAGGGAGCUGCUGGAUGAGAAAGGGCCUGAAGUCUUGCAGGACUCACUGGAUAGAUGUUAUUCAACUCCUUCAGGUUGUCUUGAACUGACUGACUCAUGCCAGCCCUACAGAAGUGCCUUUUAUGUAUUGGAGCAACAGCAUGUUGGCUUGGCUGUUGACAUGGAUGAAAUUGAAAAGUACCAAGAAGUGGAAGAAGACCAAGACCCAUCAUGCCCCAGGCUCAGCAGGGAGCUGCUGGAUGAGAAAGAGCCUGAAGUCUUGCAGGACUCACUGGAUAGAUGUUAUUCGACUCCUUCAGGUUAUCUUGAACUGCCUGACUUAGGCCAGCCCUACAGCAGUGCUGUUUACUCAUUGGAGGAACAGUACCUUGGCUUGGCUCUUGACGUGGACAGAAUUAAAAAGGACCAAGAAGAGGAAGAAGACCAAGGCCCACCAUGCCCCAGGCUCAGCAGGGAGCUGCUGGAGGUAGUAGAGCCUGAAGUCUUGCAGGACUCACUGGAUAGAUGUUAUUCAACUCCUUCCAGUUGUCUUGAACAGCCUGACUCCUGCCAGCCCUAUGGAAGUUCCUUUUAUGCAUUGGAGGAAAAACAUGUUGGCUUUUCUCUUGACGUGGGAGAAAUUGAAAAGAAGGGGAAGGGGAAGAAAAGAAGGGGAAGAAGAUCAAAGAAGGAAAGAAGAAGGGGAAGAAAAGAAGGGGAAGAAGAUCAAAACCCACCAUGCCCCAGGCUCAGCAGGGAGCUGCUGGAUGAGAAAGGGCCUGAAGUCUUGCAGGACUCACUGGAUAGAUGUUAUUCAACUCCUUCAGGUUGUCUUGAACUGACUGACUCAUGCCAGCCCUACAGAAGUGCCUUUUAUGUAUUGGAGCAACAGCAUGUUGGCUUGGCUGUUGACAUGGAUGAAAUUGAAAAGUACCAAGAAGUGGAAGAAGACCAAGACCCAUCAUGCCCCAGGCUCAGCAGGGAGCUGCUGGAUGAGAAAGAGCCUGAAGUCUUGCAGGACUCACUGGAUAGAUGUUAUUCGACUCCUUCAGGUUAUCUUGAACUGCCUGACUUAGGCCAGCCCUACAGCAGUGCUGUUUACUCAUUGGAGGAACAGUACCUUGGCUUGGCUCUUGACGUGGACAGAAUUAAAAAGGACCAAGAAGAGGAAGAAGACCAAGACCCACCAUGCCCCAGGCUCAGCAGGGAGCUGCUGGAGGUAGUAGAGCCUGAAGUCUUGCAGGACUCACUGGAUAGAUGUUAUUCAACUCCUUCCAGUUGUCUUGAACAGCCUGACUCCUGCCAGCCCUAUGGAAGUUCCUUUUAUGCAUUGGAGGAAAAACAUGUUGGCUUUUCUCUUGACGUGGGAGAAAUUGAAAAGAAGGGGAAGGGGAAGAAAAGAAGGGGAAGAAGAUCAAAGAAGGAAAGAAGAAGGGGAAGAAAAGAAGGGGAAGAAGAUCAAAACCCACCAUGCCCCAGGCUCAGCAGGGAGCUGCUGGAUGAGAAAGGGCCUGAAGUCUUGCAGGACUCACUGGAUAGAUGUUAUUCAACUCCUUCAGGUUGUCUUGAACUGACUGACUCAUGCCAGCCCUACAGAAGUGCCUUUUAUGUAUUGGAGCAACAGCAUGUUGGCUUGGCUGUUGACAUGGAUGAAAUUGAAAAGUACCAAGAAGUGGAAGAAGACCAAGACCCAUCAUGCCCCAGGCUCAGCAGGGAGCUGCUGGAUGAGAAAGAGCCUGAAGUCUUGCAGGACUCACUGGAUAGAUGUUAUUCGACUCCUUCAGGUUAUCUUGAACUGCCUGACUUAGGCCAGCCCUACAGCAGUGCUGUUUACUCAUUGGAGGAACAGUACCUUGGCUUGGCUCUUGACGUGGACAGAAUUAAAAAGGACCAAGAAGAGGAAGAAGACCAAGGCCCACCAUGCCCCAGGCUCAGCAGGGAGCUGCUGGAGGUAGUAGAGCCUGAAGUCUUGCAGGACUCACUGGAUAGAUGUUAUUCAACUCCUUCCAGUUGUCUUGAACAGCCUGACUCCUGCCAGCCCUAUGGAAGUUCCUUUUAUGCAUUGGAGGAAAAACAUGUUGGCUUUUCUCUUGACGUGGGAGAAAUUGAAAAGAAGGGGAAGGGGAAGAAAAGAAGGGGAAGAAGAUCAAAGAAGGAAAGAAGAAGGGGAAGAAAAGAAGGGGAAGAAGAUCAAAACCCACCAUGCCCCAGGCUCAGCAGGGAGCUGCUGGAUGAGAAAGGGCCUGAAGUCUUGCAGGACUCACUGGAUAGAUGUUAUUCAACUCCUUCAGGUUGUCUUGAACUGACUGACUCAUGCCAGCCCUACAGAAGUGCCUUUUAUGUAUUGGAGCAACAGCAUGUUGGCUUGGCUGUUGACAUGGAUGAAAUUGAAAAGUACCAAGAAGUGGAAGAAGACCAAGACCCAUCAUGCCCCAGGCUCAGCAGGGAGCUGCUGGAUGAGAAAGAGCCUGAAGUCUUGCAGGACUCACUGGAUAGAUGUUAUUCGACUCCUUCAGGUUAUCUUGAACUGCCUGACUUAGGCCAGCCCUACAGCAGUGCUGUUUACUCAUUGGAGGAACAGUACCUUGGCUUGGCUCUUGACGUGGACAGAAUUAAAAAGGACCAAGAAGAGGAAGAAGACCAAGGCCCACCAUGCCCCAGGCUCAGCAGGGAGCUGCUGGAGGUAGUAGAGCCUGAAGUCUUGCAGGACUCACUGGAUAGAUGUUAUUCAACUCCUUCCAGUUGUCUUGAACAGCCUGACUCCUGCCAGCCCUAUGGAAGUUCCUUUUAUGCAUUGGAGGAAAAACAUGUUGGCUUUUCUCUUGACGUGGGAGAAAUUGAAAAGAAGGGGAAGGGGAAGAAAAGAAGGGGAAGAAGAUCAAAGAAGGAAAGAAGAAGGGGAAGAAAAGAAGGGGAAGAAGAUCAAAACCCACCAUGCCCCAGGCUCAGCAGGGAGCUGCUGGAUGAGAAAGGGCCUGAAGUCUUGCAGGACUCACUGGAUAGAUGUUAUUCAACUCCUUCAGGUUGUCUUGAACUGACUGACUCAUGCCAGCCCUACAGAAGUGCCUUUUAUGUAUUGGAGCAACAGCAUGUUGGCUUGGCUGUUGACAUGGAUGAAAUUGAAAAGUACCAAGAAGUGGAAGAAGACCAAGACCCAUCAUGCCCCAGGCUCAGCAGGGAGCUGCUGGAUGAGAAAGAGCCUGAAGUCUUGCAGGACUCACUGGAUAGAUGUUAUUCGACUCCUUCAGGUUAUCUUGAACUGCCUGACUUAGGCCAGCCCUACAGCAGUGCUGUUUACUCAUUGGAGGAACAGUACCUUGGCUUGGCUCUUGACGUGGACAGAAUUAAAAAGGACGAAGAAGAGGAAGAAGACCAAGACCCACCAUGCCCCAGGCUCAGCAGGGAGCUGCUGGAGGUAGUAGAGCCUGAAGUCUUGCAGGACUCACUGGAUAGAUGUUAUUCAACUCCUUCCAGUUGUCUUGAACAGCCUGACUCCUGCCAGCCCUAUGGAAGUUCCUUUUAUGCAUUGGAGGAAAAACAUGUUGGCUUUUCUCUUGACGUGGGAGAAAUUGAAAAGAAGGGGAAGGGGAAGAAAAGAAGGGGAAGAAGAUCAAAGAAGGAAAGAAGAAGGGGAAGAAAAGAAGGGGAAGAAGAUCAAAACCCACCAUGCCCCAGGCUCAGCAGGGAGCUGCUGGAUGAGAAAGGGCCUGAAGUCUUGCAGGACUCACUGGAUAGAUGUUAUUCAACUCCUUCAGGUUAUCUUGAACUGACUGACUCAUGCCAGCCCUACAGAAGUGCCUUUUAUGUAUUGGAGCAACAGCAUGUUGGCUUGGCUGUUGACAUGGAUGAAAUUGAAAAGUACCAAGAAGUGGAAGAAGACCAAGACCCAUCAUGCCCCAGGCUCAGCAGGGAGCUGCUGGAUGAGAAAGAGCCUGAAGUCUUGCAGGACUCACUGGAUAGAUGUUAUUCGACUCCUUCAGGUUAUCUUGAACUGCCUGACUUAGGCCAGCCCUACAGCAGUGCUGUUUACUCAUUGGAGGAACAGUACCUUGGCUUGGCUCUUGACGUGGACAGAAUUAAAAAGGACCAAGAAGAGGAAGAAGACCAAGGCCCACCAUGCCCCAGGCUCAGCAGGGAGCUGCUGGAGGUAGUAGAGCCUGAAGUCUUGCAGGACUCACUGGAUAGAUGUUAUUCAACUCCUUCCAGUUGUCUUGAACAGCCUGACUCCUGCCAGCCCUAUGGAAGUUCCUUUUAUGCAUUGGAGGAAAAACAUGUUGGCUUUUCUCUUGACGUGGGAGAAAUUGAAAAGAAGGGGAAGGGGAAGAAAAGAAGGGGAAGAAGAUCAAAGAAGGAAAGAAGAAGGGGAAGAAAAGAAGGGGAAGAAGAUCAAAACCCACCAUGCCCCAGGCUCAGCAGGGAGCUGCUGGAUGAGAAAGGGCCUGAAGUCUUGCAGGACUCACUGGAUAGAUGUUAUUCAACUCCUUCAGGUUGUCUUGAACUGUGUGACUCAUGCCAGCCCUACAGAAGUGCCUUUUAUGUAUUGGAGCAACAGCGUGUUGGCUUGGCUGUUGACAUGGAUGAAAUUGAAAAGUACCAAGAAGUGGAAGAAGACCAAGACCCAUCAUGCCCCAGGCUCAGCAGGGAGCUGCUGGAUGAGAAAGAGCCUGAAGUCUUGCAGGACUCACUGGAUAGAUGUUAUUCGACUCCUUCAGGUUAUCUUGAACUGCCUGACUUAGGCCAGCCCUACAGCAGUGCUGUUUACUCAUUGGAGGAACAGUACCUUGGCUUGGCUCUUGACGUGGACAAAAUUGAAAAGAAGGGGAAGGGGAAAAAAAGAAGGGGAAGAAGAUCAAAGAAGGAAAGAAGAAGGGGAAGAAAAGAAGGGGAAGAAGAUCAAAACCCACCAUGCCCCAGGCUCAACGGCGUGCUGAUGGAAGUGGAAGAGCGUGAAGUCUUACAGGACUCACUGGAUAGAUGUUAUUCGACUCCGUCAAUGUACUUUGAACUACCUGACUCAUUCCAGCACUACAGAAGUGUGUUUUACUCAUUUGAGGAACAGCACAUCAGCUUCGCCCUUUACGUGGACAAUAGGUUUUUUACUUUGACGGUGACAAGUCUCCACCUGGUGUUCCAGAUGGGAGUCAUAUUCCCACAAUAAGCAGCCCUUAGUAAUCCGAGAGAUGUCAUUCCUGCAGGCAGGACCUAUAGGCAAGUGAAGAUUUGAAUGAAAGUACAGUUCCAUUUGGAAGCCCAGACAUAGGAUGGGUCAGUGGGCAUGGCUCUAUUCCUAUUCUCAAACCAUGCCAGUGGCAACCUGUGCGCAGUCUGAAGACAAUGGACCCACGUUAGGUGUGACACGUUCACAUAACUGUGCAGCACAUGCCGGGAGUGAUCAGUCAGACAUUUUAAUUUGAACCACGUAUCUCUGGGUAGCUACAAAAUUCCUCAGGGAUUUCAUUUUGCAGGCAUGUCUCUGAGCUUCUAUACCUGCUCAAGGUCAUUGUCAUCUUUGUGUUUAGCUCAUCCAAAGGUGUUACCCUGGUUUCAAUGAACCUAACCUCAUUCUUUGUGUCUUCAGUGUUGGCUUGUUUUAGCUGAUCCAUCUGUAACACAGGAGGGAUCCUUGGCUGAGGAUUGUAUUUCAGAACCACCAACUGCUCUUGACAAUUGUUAACCCGCUAGACUCCUUUGGUUAGAGAAGCCACAGUCCUUCAGCCUCCAAUUGGUGUCAGUACUUAGGAAGACCACAGCUAGAUGGACAAACAGCAUUGGGAGGCCUUAGCCCUGCUCCUCUCAAUUCCAUCCUGUAGAGAACAGGAGUCAGGAGCCGCUGGCAGGAGACAGCAUGUCACCCAGGACUCUGCCGGUGCAGAAUAUGAACAAUGCCAUGUUCUUGCAGAAAACGCUUAGCCUGAGUUUCAUAGGAGGUAAUCACCAGACAACUGCAGAAUGUAGAACACUGAGCAGGACAACUGACCUGUCUCCUUCACAUAGUCCAUAUCACCACAAAUCACACAACAAAAAGGAGAAGAAAUAUUUUGGGUUCAAAAAAAGUAAAAAGAUAAUGUAGCUGCAUUUCUUUAGUUAUUUUGAACCCCAAAUAUUUCCUCAUCUUUUUGUUGUUGUCAUGGAUGGUGGUGACAUGGACUUGUUUAUAGAAGACAGGUCAGCUGUCUGGCUCAAUGAUCUACAUUCUGAAGUUGUCUGAAAAUGUCUUCAUGAUUAAAUUCAGCCUAAACGUUUUGCCAGGAACACUGCAGAGACAAUGCUGUGAGUUUCCAACCUCAGCCCAUCUGCGGGCAGAGAAGGUCUAGUUUGUCCAUCACCAUUAUGAUAUCAGGACUGGUUACUUGGUUAAGGAGGGGUCUAGGAGAUCUGUCCCUUUUAGAGACACCUUACUUACAAUGAAGUACUUGGGAAAGUGGUUUUCAAGAGUAUAAAUAUCCUGUAUUCUAAUGAUCAUCCUCUAAACAUUUUAUCAUUUAUUAAUCCUCCCUGCCUGUGUCUAUUAUUAUAUUCAUAUCUCUACACUGCAAAUUUGGGGUCUCAAUUUUUACUGUGCCUUUGUUUUUACUAGUGUCUGCUGUUGCAAAAAGAAGACAUUCUCUGCCUGAGUUUUAAUUUUUGUCCAAAGUUAAUUUUAAUCUAUACAAUUAAAACCUUUUGCCUAUCACUCUGGACUUUUGGAUUGUUUUUUACAUUCAGUGUUAUAAUAUUUGAUUAUGGUGAUUGGUUUUGGUGGGUACUGAUGCGAAUUAAUAAAAA